GCGCGUCGAGAGGCGACGGCGGGCUGGCCUGGCGCGCUGCGGCGCUCGCUCACCCGCUCCCGAGGAAGGGCAGUGGGCCCCGCCGCCGCCUCCCAAUGGCGAGGCUGCGGGAUUGCCUGCCCCGCCUGAUGCUCACGCUCCGGUCCCUGCUCUUCUGGUCCCUGGUCUACUGCUACUGCGGGCUCUGCGCCUCCAUCCACCUGCUCAAACUUUUGUGGAGCCUCGGCAAGGGGCCGGCGCAGACCUUCCGGCGGCCCGCCCGGGAGCACCCUCCCGCGUGCCUGAGCGACCCCUCCUUGGGCACCCACUGCUACGUGCGGAUCAAGGAUUCAGGGUUAAGAUUUCACUAUGUUGCUGCUGGAGAAAGAGGCAAACCACUUAUGCUGCUGCUUCAUGGAUUUCCAGAAUUCUGGUAUUCUUGGCGUUACCAACUGAGAGAAUUUAAAAGUGAAUAUCGAGUUGUAGCACUGGAUUUGAGAGGUUAUGGAGAAACAGAUGCUCCCAUUCAUCGACAGAAUUAUAAAUUGGAUUGUCUAAUUACAGAUAUAAAGGAUAUUUUAGAUUCUUUAGGGUAUAGCAAAUGUGUUCUUAUUGGCCAUGACUGGGGGGGCAUGAUUGCUUGGCUAAUUGCCAUCUGUUAUCCUGAAAUGGUGAUGAAGCUUAUUGUUAUUAACUUCCCUCAUCCAAAUGUAUUUACAGAAUAUAUUUUACGACACCCUGCUCAGCUGUUGAAAUCCAGUUAUUAUUACUUCUUCCAAAUACCAUGGUUCCCAGAAUUUAUGUUCUCAAUAAAUGAUUUCAAGGUUUUGAAACAUCUGUUUACCAGUCACAGCACUGGCAUUGGAAGAAAAGGAUGCCAAUUAACAACAGAGGAUCUUGAAGCUUAUAUUUAUGUCUUUUCUCAGCCUGGAGCAUUAAGUGGCCCAAUUAACCAUUACCGAAAUAUCUUCAGCUGCCUGCCUCUCAAACAUCACAUGGUGACCACUCCAACACUACUACUGUGGGGAGAGAAUGACGCAUUCAUGGAGGUUGAGAUGGCUGAAGUCACAAAGAUUUAUGUUAAAAACUAUUUCAGGCUAACUAUUUUGUCAGAAGCCAGUCAUUGGCUUCAGCAAGACCAACCUGACAUAGUGAACAAAUUGAUAUGGACAUUUCUAAAAGAAGAAACAAGAAAAAAAGAUUGACUUUUCUUUAUCUUCUAUGAAGGGUCUGUAAUGAAAUCUCUAAAUAAUUUUUAAAAAUUGUUCAUCAACUUCUUUAUGUUUUAUUAGAAAAAAACUGUUUUAAUGUGCUUUAUCAUAAAUAAAUAUCCUGACAAAUGGUAUUGAAAAAAAUCUGAGAUCAUGUGAACAUAUAAUACAAUGUUGAUUUUCUUCUGGUGUAUUUUGCACAGACAAGCAUCUGCCUUAAAAUAUAUACACUUGUACAAAAAGGAA